AGUCUCCGUGUGAGUGCGCGUAGUCGCGCGCCUGUCCCCGCGCGGGCUCCGUAGCGCGUGUGCAGGCUGACGCAGCUCGCGGGCCCUCCUCCUGCUCUGCAGCGGCGUCGGCGGAGUUUUGGGCGUUUGGGAGGGGGGCGAGGGAGAGAGAGUCGAGAGAGGGAGGCGGCGGUGGGGAGGAGGAGGAGGAGGAGGAGCAGGCGCCGCCAUGGCCGCCGCUAUCACCGACAUGGCCGACCUGGAGGAGCUCUCCCGCCUGAGCCCUCUGCCCCCCGGCAGCCCGGGUUCGGCGGCGCGGGGCCGGGCUGAGCCCCCCGAGGAGGAGGAGGAAGAGGAGGAGGAGGAAGAGGAGGCGGAGGCCGAGGCGGUGGCGGCGCUGCUGCUGAACGGCGGCAGCGGUGGGGGCGGCGGAGGCGGCGGCGGAGGAGUGGGGGGCGGCGAGGCAGAGACGAUGUCGGAGCCGAGCCCCGAGAGCGCCAGCCAGGCCGGGGAGGACGAAGACGAGGAGGAGGACGACGAGGAGGAGGAAGAUGAGAGCAGCAGCAGCGGCGGGGGUGAGGAGGAGAGUAGCGCCGAGAGCCUGGUGGGCAGCAGCGGCGGGAGCAGCAGCGACGAGACCCGCUCGUUGAGCCCCGGCGCCGCCAGCAGCAGCAGCGGGGAUGGGGACGGCAAGGAGGGCCUGGAGGAGCCCAAGGGACCGCGGGGCAGCCAGGGCGGCGGCGGGGGCGGCAGCAGUAGCAGCAGCGUAGUCUCCAGCGGCGGCGACGAGGGCUACGGGACUGGGGGAGGCGGAAGCAGCGCGACCUCCGGGGGCCGGCGGGGCAGCUUGGAGAUGUCGUCGGAUGGGGAACCCCUGAGCCGCAUGGACUCGGAGGACAGCAUAAGCAGUACUAUAAUGGAUGUAGACAGCACAAUUUCCAGUGGGCGUUCAACUCCAGCAAUGAUGAAUGGACAAGGAAGCACUACUUCUUCAAGCAAAAAUAUUGCCUAUAAUUGUUGUUGGGACCAGUGCCAGGCUUGCUUCAACUCUAGCCCAGAUCUGGCAGAUCACAUCCGUUCCAUACAUGUAGAUGGUCAGCGAGGAGGGGUAUUUGUUUGCUUAUGGAAAGGUUGUAAAGUAUAUAACACUCCAUCUACCAGUCAAAGUUGGUUACAAAGGCAUAUGCUGACACACAGUGGAGACAAACCUUUCAAGUGUGUUGUUGGUGGCUGCAAUGCCAGCUUUGCUUCUCAGGGAGGGCUAGCUCGUCAUGUACCCACACACUUCAGUCAGCAGAACUCCUCAAAAGUUUCUAGCCAGCCAAAGGCCAAAGAAGAAUCUCCUUCUAAAGCUGGAAUGAACAAAAGGAGGAAAUUAAAGAACAAAAGACGACGCUCAUUACCACGGCCACAUGAUUUCUUCGAUGCACAAACACUGGAUGCGAUAAGACAUCGAGCCAUAUGCUUUAACCUCUCAGCUCAUAUAGAAAGUUUAGGGAAGGGACACAGUGUUGUUUUUCAUAGUACUGUAAUAGCUAAGAGAAAAGAAGAUUCUGGGAAGAUCAAACUUUUGCUUCAUUGGAUGCCUGAAGACAUUCUGCCUGAUGUGUGGGUGAAUGAAAGUGAACGACAUCAGUUAAAAACUAAAGUAGUUCAUUUAUCAAAGCUACCCAAAGAUACUGCCUUGCUUUUGGACCCAAACAUAUACAGAACAAUGCCGCAGAAGAGGUUGAAGAGGUAAAAAAUAAAUAAAUACAUAAAAAGCAAACAAGCGGGGACACCUGCAGUCUUAGUCACUGACAAUGGGUUUAGGGAAAGUUGCACAUUAGAGUCAACCCCUUCUUUUUUUUUUUUUUUUUUUUAAAUCCAGUAUUUAGGAUAAUAUUUAUGCUUAGUGUAAACAUUCUGUGAAUGAAGUAGACUCUUCGGUGGAAUAUAUUAAUAUAUUACUGUAUAUCCACAUUUUCAUGGAAUGGUACUGUGGGAGACUGAGCAAACACUCUUUUGGCAACUUAGUAGAACAGCUUCUUAAAGGCUUUGCAUGCUUGCUGCUUUAAGCUGCUUUUUUUUUUCUUUUCUUCCCUUUAGUGAUUUCAGUAGUUUAUAUUGGAAAGAAAAACAAUUACAACAUGUGCCCUUACAAAUACCAAAAGCACUGUAAGGAUAUUUGUCUUGACAGUGUUUAUUGAUUUGAAGUCAUAUUAGGAAAUAUUUAGACAAUGAAAAUUAUCAAGAGAUAAUUUACCUUUCAAUUAUGAUAAAUAGAUGUGAUUGGUUGCCAUUUGUGUUCUUUUGCAGAACUCUGAUAAGAAAAGUGUUCAAUUUGUAUUUAAGCAAACAGUGAACGACGUUUGCAAUCAACUAAAAAUUCGUCUAUCGAAUUAGGGCUGAAAAUUACUGUUAAAGAGUGUUGCAGUAUGUCUGGUGGCUCCCUUUUCAGGACUAGGGCUUUCUCAUGGAGUACAGUAUGUUAAUAUUUACCUAUAUAACUAAUCUGUUAACGGUUUUUGAAAAACCUUUCAAAUUAUUUGAAUAAUCUUCAUAUUUUCAUUUAACCUAUAUGACUCUAAUUUUUUUUCUGAGGAAAUCAUUUGGUUUUUGAGUUGUUUUUUCUUAAUGUAAGAAAAAUUGUAUUUUUUUUACAAGUAUCUUCAAACUGAAUCUUUUAUGCACCAAAGUUGGUCUUGAAAAGGAAAAUAAAAUCACUUUCUUGCUUGGUAAGCAAGAAGCCAUAUCGAUUUUUUUUAACUUACAGAAAUGGAAAUAUGUGUAACUUGUUAGUAUUGUAUUAAACAAAUGUUGCAUAGAGAUAAUAGAACAUUGCUUGUAAAUAAUUCAGCAGAUUUGUAAUAUAUUUUUAUAUUUUGAAAUGUACUGUAGAUGUUUUCUAGAGGCAUGAAAGUUAAAUGUAUAUAUUAUGGUAGAAAUAAUAUUGAAGGAUAUUGUACUUCACUAGUGCUGCCAGAGGAAUUGUUAAUAAAAGCACCUUCUUUAACAAUAAAUGUCUUUCACAGACUUAAGGGACUAUGUACUACUGUUAAUAUCUCUAAGAACAAAACACAUUGAACAUCCUUCCAGAAAGUCUUUGAGGGAGGACCUAUACCCAUAAUAGAAUUAUGGCACUCAUUUCUGACAGUGAUCAAGAAAUCAGUUAUUUCCUUACUGUUGGAAGGACAUUGUAAAGUAUGUGGUUAUAUGCAGUGAAACUGCAGAAAAUACUCCUGGUUGAGGAGUUUUCACUUUACUACAGUGAUAUAAAAACCAGCAGUUUUUACACUAAAUUUUUUAAAGAAAUAUUAGACAAAAAUAUAGAAUUAAAACCUUUGGUUCCAAAAUGGGAAAGGUUCCACGAUACAUAAAUCAUUUCUCAUUUGCUUUAAAAAAUUUAAAAGUGUAAAAAUUAUGAGAGACUUUAUUCGUUAACAAUGGGGGUAAAGAGCUAUAUACAUGAAAAUGAGUCUUAUAAAAUUAAGUGAAGUGCAAAUAAAAGCACUGCUACUAUAAGACAUUCUGGAAUGGUUGUUUAAUAAGGGUAUUAUCCAUUUGAUCUAUAGCAAUGUGAUUUUAUUUUUAAAAAGAAAAGCAGUGUGUUUUCUUUUUUUGUUGUUUUCUUUUGCUUAAGCACUUCAUCAAUUGCUUUAUUCUGUAUCUGCGAAGUAAUCUGCAAUCUCUUUUGUUCUUUUUAAAAUUUGAUUUGUUAUAAAAUUGCCAAAUAGAAGUGUUUCAGAUACAUAGUUUGUACCUGUAUUUUUAUUUUAUUGCCUCAUGUUCUUGUAAGUCAUUCUUAAUUGACCAAUGAUUGUAGACCUUGCUUGAGUAUUUUUUCUAAUAAAACAAAGCAAAUCACAUUUAGCUUCAAAUUGUAACAAUUCAAUUGAAUUUUAAAAUGACACCUGAAAAGAUACAUCUGAUAUUUUCUAUAUAGAGCACAGUAAAUAAGUUUUUUCAUUGUGUAGAAAUACUUAGAUGUCAAAACCAGAUUUCGUGAUCCUUGAUUAACUUCUGAGUACUCAAUCAAUCAUAAUCCUUUUGCUGCUUAUCUGAUGUUGGUUUGAUACUGUUAACACACCAAAAAGAAUAUGGAAUUGAAAUGAGCUAGCUUUAUAACUUGUAUGUAUACAUAUAUACACAUAACAUCCAAUUAUGACUGGGUAAUAAGUGUGAAAAUUUUAAUUUGUGGUUUUCAUUUAUUAAUGUCUGCCCAUCUGUAUUGUUGCUCCUACCUUCAAAUAUGACACCUGAAAUAAUAAGUCUGUUGUCCAGAAUUUAUGUAUUGUUCAGCAUCAAGCAAACUACAGCUCACAAGCAUACCCAUUUAUAUGUUGUCUAUGCCUGCUUUCUCCUGCAGUGGCAGAAUUGAGUGGUGAGACCUUAGGUCCUGCAAGCCCCCAAUUUUUACUACAGGUUGGCAAUCCCUAAUCCAAAAAUCUGACAUAAAAAAUGCUCCAAAGUUCAAAACUUUCUGAGUGCUGACAUCAUGCUGCAAGUGGAAAAUUCCACGCCUGACCUCAUGUGACUGGUCAUAGUCAAAACAAUUAAGACUUUGUUUCAUGCACAAAAUUAUUAAAACUGUUGUAUAAAAUUACCUUCAGUCUAUGUGUAUAAGGUGUUUGUGAGAUAUAAAUGAACUUUAUGUUUAGUCUUGGAUCGCAUUUCUGAGUCUCAUUAUGUAUAUGCAGAUACUCAAAAAUCUGAAAAAAAUCAAAAAUCUGAAAUACUUCUGGUCCCAAGCAUUUCGGAUAAGGGAUACUCAGCCUGUCUCUGGUCCUUUAAGAAAAAGUUUUCGAUUCCUUUGUCUAGUUGACAAAAAGUUUGGAAACAUAAACUUAGACCACACAACUUGCAUUUUAAUAUGACAAUGUUGAUCUUGGUAAUAAGCCAGUACAUUAAAUUUUAGUGAAAGCUGUUUCAUGUAUUUUACAGUAAAUACUGCCAUAUUAGGUACCUACAACAAAUGGUGGUUUUUGGAAACUUUUACGGUGGGUUUUUAAAGUUAUUAAUAGUCCAUCAUUUCAUCAUUUGUGUUUCUGUAUUUAUUUUGCUAAGAACUAAAUAAGAUUUUGUACAUCAGAUUGUGUUUGAACCGUAAGGCACAUCUGCUUUAUCUAAAAGAAUCUUAAGGUGGAAAUAGUGUAAAAUUUAAAAUUUUUUAUAUUUCUAAUAAACUUUUUAUAUAUAAAUGUUACCUAAAGUGGACACAUGUUACUUCUGAAUUUCACAUGAAAGGAAAUUAAAGAUGGACAAUAAUUAUCUCUCAAUAUUUUAAGAUUUGUUUUACUAAUUGAAAACAGUAUGUCAGUAAAUCUUUGGCCUUAGUGCUUUUUUCCCCCUUUUACACAUUAAUAAAAUGUUUUAAAUAUGGUAAUACUCUUAAAACGGUAGAAUUUGCCACAGUUGUUUAAAGCAUUUUUAUUUUUUCUUUGAAUUCUUAAUUCAUGGUGAACAGAUGUUGGGUUCUUAAAAUAUAAAAAUGAGAAAAUAUGUAUUAAAAAUACUUGAUAGAGGGUUUUCUCUUUAAUCACAACUUAAAAAAAGAAACCUUUAAUACCUCUGCAUAAGUUCUCUGAAAGAACUUAAAUUCUUAGUUUAUAUGAAAACUGAUAUGUAUGUCUGUGUAACAAAGCCUGUUGGGUACAGGUCUACAAGGAGAUACUUUGUUUCUAAAAAAGGAGUUAAAUCGUGUCACCUGAAUUUUUUUUUUUUGAGAUAAGUGGACAUUUUGGGGAUUUUGGUUAAAACAUAUUUCUCUAUUCUAAAAAUUACAGAAUAUGUAUUCAUAAAAGGGAAGAAAUUGUUAGAAAAUUUCCUGUGUACGUAGUUUGUUUUUAAAUUAAAGAAUCUUGUGACCUGG